AGGAGUAAGUGGAGAGGUAGAGGGCAGAAGAAAAGGGGUCAAGAAGGCAGGACCCCGUGAAGCACACCUUUCCUAAGGAUUUUGACGAAUGAGAAUGAAGAUAAACUGUGAGUUGAAAGUGAAAGAGAAAGCAUAAGGGAUCUUAGGUGCAUCUGACAAGCCUUAGAUGACCUCCAGCAACUUCAGUUCUCACCGAAUUACUGCAUUUCAGCCUUACUGAGAAGCAGCCAGUCAUACUAUCCUCAAAUUUUAACCCAGGAUGAGUUAUCCUACUAAAGAAGGAAGUGAUACAGCUGGAAAUGCUCACAAAAAUUCUGAAAAUGAGCCUCCUAAUGACUGUAGUACAGACAUAGAGUCUCCAUCUGCUGAUCCCAAUAUGAUCUAUCAGGUAGAAACCAACCCAAUAAACAGGGAGCCAGGCACAGCAACCUCCCAGGAAGAUGUUGUUCCUCAAGCAGCAGAAAACAGCGAGCUCGAAACAGAGAUCCAAAAAGAUCAACGAGAAGAAGAUCUAAAAGAAGAGCUUCUUCUACUUCAGACCCCCAUUCCCAGAAAAUUGGUCUCUCACAAGCCCUUAAAUGAUAGAUCAAGAUCCCACUCAGGGAAAGUUGAGAUGAAAGCAAACAAUUUCCCCAUAAAUCACAAAACUCGUUUUCGACUUUCAACUUCAUGGAGAGUCCCAUUUAUUAACAGUCAUGAGAUAAGAAGUAUGAUUCUCCAUCUGCUAUGUGAUAGAUAUUUCUCUCAGGCUGCAGGGUGUCAGAAUACCAUGUGGGUAAAGCGAAAAUAUAUAGCAUGUCUUUACCAUCCAAAUAGUUUCACCCAUCACGAGAGAGCCAUAACAUUUAGAAGGCCUUCGAGGGUGCACUACUACCGUCCCCUCACUGAGAGAAUGACAUCAGGAAAAUUUUGCAAAUCAACUGACACUAAAGGGAAAUGUAGAUUCCGUGCUAUUGUGAGGUCUGUGCUCUUUGUGUCACAGAUACAAAUUGAAAGUAUUUUUAAUAUAAAAGGUUUUGUGGAUAUAUUGACAUAUAUCCAUACCAUGAAUGUUAUGAUCACAAACACCAAUAAUGGUUGGAAAUACUUUUGUCCCAUCUGUGGAAGGCUUUUUAACACUUACUCUGAAUUAAGACAACAUUCAUGCAGCUCUUCUGGGAAUUAAAUUAAAUUGGGGUAAAUUCAUUUUAAAAUAUAACUUCUAAAAUUCAUAAUUUGACUACUAAAGUAAGACAAAAUUGCAUGAACAUAAAUUUUAGUAUUAUUAGAGGGAGUAGCAGAAAGGAACACAAACUAAUAGUACCUCUCAGUAAGAAAUACCUAUGGGGAGUGAGGAAACAUCUGUUUAUACUUUGCUUUUACAAGUACAUCAUUGAAAUAUCAGACCUGUCAUCUAUAUUGAGUCAGCAUUUGAACCAAGUAAAUGUUUUCACUGUCUUAACAUCUAUUUCUGUAGAUGUAAAUAUUGUUAACAUAAAAGAAUCCAAGUUAACAGGAUCCUGACUAAGAUAGCAAACAUAUAUUGGAAGGCCAGACAAAGUUCUACCAAGUGUUUCCAGAGAUUCUGCUACAUGUAUUAUCUGAAAUGUUCUCCAUAUAUUCAAUAAAAACCAAUUUGAAGACAUA